AGGCGCGAUGUUGACGGGGUCCUAAGAUGGCUGCUGGGCGACCACUUCCUGACAGCUCCAGUUAAUGGGACUGCCAGCAGGCUAGACAUCCUUCGCCGGAAUGUGCAGCGCUUAGUUCUGUGCCCGGGAGGGGCUUCUCUCUCUUUUGGGAUUGGAGUGUGGCAUUGCCGCCAGAAAGCCUGCAGAAUUCCGGGUUGUGCAGCCAAGCAGGAACGGUGUACCUUUCUAGACCCAUCCUCUUGCAAUCUUGGACCCUGUUAAUCACAAUAUGGGACAGAAAACUGCAAAACAAAUUUCCGUCCUUCCAUUUUAUUCCUUCAUAUUGAUAGUAAAUCAUGAGCAGUACAACCGGCUUCUCUAUUUUAAGCAUCUUUUGAAGGAACUGGUUUUGGCUCAAUAUAUGUGCUAAAAUAGACUGUGCCAUGAAGAUCAAUAGUGAAAGAAAAGAUGUGGAGUGGGCUGCUACCUCCUGGCCUAAAUGAAAGUGACGCUGAGUCAAACUCGGAAGAUGAAGCUACGUUGGAGAACUCUGGACUUAACUUACAGGAAGAUAAAGAGGAUGAGAGCAUCAGAAAAACAGAAAUCAUAGAUUUCUCAACAGAUGAACCAAAAACUGAAACAGAGUCAAAUGUAAAUGCCUAUGAAGAGUGUCCUUCUGGAAUUCCCAUAGAUAUGUGGAAUAAAUUUCAAGAAUUGCAUAAAAAACAUUCUGAACAGAAAAGCACAACCUCAAGAUUCAGAGGGAAAAGAAGAAAACGCUCCAGAAAAGAUAAAUUGAAGAAUGAAAAAGAAUUACAUAGUGAACCGUCCUCAAAUGAAACCCAGUGGAAAGAGCUUACUCAGUAUUUUGGAGUCAAUGAUAGAUUUGACCCGCCUGUUAAAAGGAAAAAAGUUGAGAAGUCAGGCCUUGAAAAGAGGAUAGACCAGGCUGUGGAGGAGUGGAAUAUUGAGAAGGCUGAGGAACUCAGCAACCAGCUAGCUACUCGAGAGCUUGGUGUAAAAAUUGCCAAAGCAGUUGCCUGCCACAACUUUGUAAAAGCCAAAAAGGAGGUUGAAAAUUCACAGGCUGCCCGAAAAAAGAAGAAACUUGCAUGGGGGUUUGAAGCAAAGAAGAGAUGGGAAACCAAAAGCAACAUGGGAUACAUGUAACUUGCCAGAGUGCUUCAAGACAUUUGUAGACUCAAAUGCUCAAUUUACUGAGAAUGUUUUCCUGCCUAUGUUAAUAUGUCAGAAAAUUGAUAGCACUAAAACAAAAAUAAGCAUAAAAUUUGGGAUUUUGAUUAUCAGCUCUUUUCAGUCUUUCUUUAAGGACUUUGUCCUAUUGAAGUGAAUAAAAUGAAGCAUUCUGUUAUUUGUAUAAGAAAUGUAAGAAAAAAAAUAUAGAAAGAAGAGGAUAGGAUUUUGUUUAUUUGUAUGGAUGGACCCUUGGUAUAAAAUCACUUUUGGCGCUUUCCAUUCAUUUGGUUUAGCACAGCCAGUGAGCUUCUCGUACUUUCUUUCUUUUUUUUUUUUUUUUUGAGACAGAGCCUCGCUUGCUCUGUCACCCAGGCUAGAGUGCAGUAGCACGAUCUUGGCUCACUGCAACCACUGCUUCCUGGGUUCAAGUGAUUCUCAUGCCUCAGCCUCCUGAGUAGCUGGGAUUAUGGACAAAUGCCACCACACCCGGCUAAUUUUUUUUUUUUUUUUGUAUUUUUAGUAGAGACAGAGUUUUGCUGUGUUGGUCAGGCUGGUCUUGAACUCCUGGCCUCAUAUGAUUCACCUGCCUCUGCCUCCCAAAGUUCUGGGAGUACAGACAUGAGCUACCAUGCUGCCCUUGUAUUUUCUUAUCUGUACCCAGUGUAACUACACGUUUACUGGAACUGUGUUUUUAAGACUGACAGUUGUUUAUAAUGGAUUAGUCGUAAGUACCAAAAAGUCUCAGUUGAUAUUAUCUUUACAAAUGACUUGACCUUAAUGUUAUAAAAGUAGUUACUGUUUUUUUUUAAUUGGAGGCAGACUUGAUAUUUCAGAGUUGCAUAGUAAAAGCAAUUUGUUAAUUUUUGUGUACUUUCAGAUAAACUAUUACAAUAAAGAAAGGAGCAGAAUGUAGUAUUUGGAAGAUGAUUUAAAUUCAGCAACGCCUAAAAAUGUCUUCCUAAGUAUUUUUCUCAGCCAUGUCAUUCUUUAAAUUAUGAGAUGGUUCUUAGAAGAGAAAAUGGUGUAAUUGUAUUAAACAGACAAUUAUAACUCAAGAUAAUAUAACUUUGAACCUUCUAAGAACUGAUUUGUUUGGUUUUCCUCCCAUUCCCCAUUCCUCCUUAAAAGAUUGAAUGAAUUAAUGAGCAGAAAGAGAGGAUUGGUAACAUGGGAAAUCGUUUUCAUUAGAUGUACAUUUCCUGGUUCUGACAGGAAAGGGGCUCCAGAAAAUCAUAAAACAAGCAGGUGAACAAGACCAGGUGUGUCGGCACCUCCCUGCUCAGUGCCCAGCGGAGGUAAAGAACCACUCAGCAUGGUUUUUGUCAGUUCACCUCUUCUGUCGUUGUCAGAGGUUUCCUACCUGUCUGAUAUAAACUUUCUCUGGGUUGAUAAUAUAAAUUCAGAAACAUGUAAAAUGAAUCAUGAUUAUAUUACUGUUAUUUUUAGACUUAAAAUAGUAACAAAAUUUUAUUUAUGGUGGCACAUUUAAUGGCUUUUUUUUUCUGUGUUCUGGAAUAAGAGAAUACCUAGCUACUAUUUAAGCAUCCAAAAAUCAUAUCUUGCUUUCAUUUAGUUGAGAAAAGCCAGCAUAGAGAAAGCAAAGUUUUAGAAUAUUAUGUGUCAUACUAAUUCAGUAUCCAGACCAAAUGUUGGAAAGUCUUAUUUUAUGAUUUAAUAUCCCUUGUUCCAUUUUACAGAUAUGAUCAUGUAAAACUUACCUACAAUAUUCAUUUCAAACUGCUAAAUUAGGUAAAUACAGACUUUUAGUAUAGAAACCUUUCCUCUAAAAAUCCAUUAUGGGGGAAAUAUUCACUAUACAAUCCAGUGGUUUUGUCUGAAAUCCUAAAAAUGUUAUUUUUGAGCAGGCGAGUGGUAUAGAUAUUCUCACACUUGGGGCCCCGAUAUGGGCAUUUCCCUUUGACUUCAGUCUCAUUUUUUUUUUUUUUUCUGUUUCUACUCCUUAGAGCAUUUAGUGACCCCUGCAGGCAUGUUGCACUUCCCAUACUGAAGCCUUGCCAGAGUGGCCUCCUGUAGGGUCUGACUUGGGAUCCUGUCCAGCCAAGGAAGCCCUUCUUCAGCCUGCUCCAGUGCCCGCAGUUGCCCCCUCAGCAUCCCCUCGGGGUUCUCAUGUAGAUGGGAACAUUUUAACUACGCGGAAGGCAGGCAUUUCAGCAGAAUUAAGUAUAGCGGGGGCUCAUCUAAUAAAGGAAGCCACUUCUCCCAAGUCGUCACUCCUUUCUGGGCAUGGGUUGUGGAAAGCUCUAAAACGUUAUGUGUAGCAGAAGAAGGGGUUGGAGGGAAGAUUUGUGGGGACAGGUUGUCUUGGAUUGGCCCUGCUGACAUGUCAUUUGAGAGCAGUUUUAUUUUAUCCUUUCUAAUAGGAAUUAGGUAUUUUACUCCUAGAAACAUUAUUCCUUGAGUACGCAUGCUGCUCAAAGGAUGUAGUCAUUUGUCCACUCCAUUCUAGUCACAGCAAAAUAAGGAUUCUUUUUGGAUCAGUAAUAACUUUGGUUCCUAAAACUUCAAUAUGUGCAUUUACUACCACCAGAAUGCCUGAGUUAGAUCAGUAAUGUAAACGUCAGUUAUUGUUAACUGAGAUUAAUAUGUUUCAGGCCGUUGGUAUGGCAUUAAUGUAACUAUGAUUUACUAUUUAAGUACUUUAGGCUAAAACAUCUUACUAAAGAACAGUAAUUUUGAGCUUUACAGCACUGGUUCUGAGAAAGGGAAGUUGGCAGUGCAUUCUUGUUUGGGAGCCCUCAGGAUGUUUCUGAUUUUCAGCAGAACAUUCUAUGUCUUUCACCGAAAGGAGAGAUUGAAUAUAUAAUCUUAGGUUUGCUAUAAUUAGUUCUGAUGACAGAGUUAAAUACCUCAGCCAAGACUGUAAAUCAGUACGUAAACAGGUUUCUGCAACUGAUCAUAAAUCUCAAACUGCAUAUUUUAAACACUUAUUUUUUUAGGAUGACAGAUAAGGGAGCAGCAGGCUAAGGAUAGGAAUAAAAUGUUAUCUGAACUUUUAAGUCACAACUUAGAACUCACAUUAAAAUCUUCUGAUUUUCUUUAUACCUUUUGUCUAAAAUAUUAUCUUUUAGCUUAUUAAUAACUUUAAUAAGACAAGUUUGAAUUUAAUUCACAAAAAAUGAAGAUAUAAUUUAUAAAAUGUCCAAAUUUUUGUUAAGACAUUACUUUUUAAGAAAUGUGUGUCUUGCUAAAUAUAAAACAUAUUGUAUGAGGUUGUUGUUUAAACAAAAUGAGAGUUGUACAUUAUUUUUUAAGAGAUGAUAAAGUUUGAGGAGGCAAGCCGAUGUUAUGUCAGAUCUCAUUUUGAAGUUAGUGAAACCUAGUCUAAUCCAGAACCAACUGAAUCCAAGUUUUCCAUUUUGGCAGAAGUUGCUUUUAUUUUUAGUAUCUGGCAGAGCAACAAAUGCUUUGCAUGUCAGUUCAAUAUUUUUUCCUGCCAACUGUUUAUUCAUUGGCUUAAAAUUUACACUCUACUAAAGUCUUAGCUCUGACUUUCAUGAAACAAAUAGUAAUAUUUGGACAAAAUAUGUACAUGAAAAUCUUUUUCCAGAACCAAAUGUAGACUGGUAUUUGUGACAUCAGUGCCUUCUAGCAUGGUGACGGGUCGAAAAAUACUUUGAAAAGUUGAAGGCUGUGUAAACCCACGGCAGUGCAUCUCAAGUGAUUUUUAUUAUGAGGUAAUCAGAGUAUCUAGGUUUUCAAAUUUAAAUUAGUGGGUGACUUUAUGCUAGAAAGUAGAAUAUGUGUUAGAAUAAAUUUAUCAAUAUAUAUUCUUGGCCUUUGUAGGAUACUGAGACAAUAAGGUCCAUUUUUCAUUUUUGAGGUUGGGGAGCUCUGUAGAUUUUGAUAAAAUGUGCAGAACUGCAUUCUUUAAUCUUUAUUAUUUCAUCCUCCCUCCACACUGCUUGCUUUAAAAGAAAAAAAUACCUACACACAUUUUCUAGUGUUAACUGCUGUAAUCAGCAUAGACUUCCUGGGAAGGGAUUCUUGCCUUCAGUAAAGGACAUGACAGCAUGUGGCCAAUGGAGAUUGCCACGAGGAAACCUGGAAAGGCAUUGAACCAUUUUGUGCUACUGUUAAAAUGAGGUGUGUUGUCUCUUUAUUAUCUCCUACUCAAUAGUGAGUAUUCUGGAGGUGUCUGUUCCCUUUCCGGAAUUUCUUCAAAUACAGAGAUGCUUCAGAGUAGCUUCCUGCCACAUUGGCUUUCAUGAUCUUAAUCCCUGGAACACAGCUAUAGGCUUCUGGGAGAUAGUUUAUUAAAUGCCAUGCAGAAUGCUAUGUUUUUAGAUGUGCAUGUAAAUCAAGAAUUAGCUGAGGAAUAUCUUUUUAUUAGUAGUAGUAGUAACUCAUUUUUAGAUUCAAGUAAAGUUUGUUUUCCAGGUGAGAUGACAUUUUUAAGAAAUUGAAUUUAAGUAUGUGCUUUUAUAUCCGGACCAGGUUUCUCAAGGAAGCAGAAUACAAGGGAAUGAAAGGGGAAGGGAGGGUAGUGCCCAAGAGAAACCUCGGCUCCUAAGUGCUCCCCUGCCAGGUUUCCCCCGUGCCUGCCCACUGGCACCAUCCUGGCAGCUCCAGCCCACACCCCCUCCUGGACCCUGGGCUGCCUCUCGCUGAAUAGCUGCAGGGGGCCUGCUAUGUGACAGGUAUGGAAUGAGGUAAUCCUUUUCCACCUCUAAUUUCUGAAGGGUGUGUCUGUCCAGUUUUUACUUGUUCAUUGAAUUUAAAGCCUUAGGAACCAACAGCUACAGUGCAAGCUGUAAUUAUUGAUGUCUGUUUCAUAUUCAUCUGUAAGUUCUGGCAUUUGAUCAAGAAGUCAAUAUAUCACUUCAUCUUCAGGCUGAAUGUGUCUCAGCUAUAAAGGUUUUAUUGUUUGAUGGAUAGCAUACAAUUAUGACUGCCCACAAUAAAAAGUGUUUUCAUUUGUAAGAUGGGUGAUACUAGAAGUAAUUAUGAAUGUCACAAGGAAUAGUGAAACAAUGAAGCUUUGCGUUUCUUUGAAUUUCUCCCUACAUAAUGCCCAAGGAACAUUUCCUGAAUGCCUACUAUAUGUCAGAUAAACUAACUCUUGCAGAUGCAAGGAUGAAUAAGCAAAAUCUAAUAGGAAAUAUAUGUAAACCAUGUUUUGAACAACUCCAUUUUCAGGCGGGCUAUUAGAAAAUCAGUGAGUUUUUCUUUGCUGAAUACAAAGACAUAAUCUACAUAUAAGAAGUAAUGUAGACUUAAAAAUUUUAGUUACCUGAGUAUAUACUUACUGUACAGGUUGCUGAAUUUCCUAGCUAGGCAGUCAGCUACAGUGGCUUAUCAGCUUAGUGACUGAUCCAUACUUGCUCACAUCAGAGUGGGUGGGAUUGAUGCCCUGACUGUCUCCCCUGGAGAUGAGGAGCAUUGGUGGGGUUUGACUCAGGAAUGAAUGCAAAUGUUUGUUCUGCACAUUACUCAGUGAUUUUAAGCUUAAAGUUUUCUUAGACUGCAUUAACGUGUCCUUUAUUUUAGCUUGGGUGGGCCACAGUACCUUCCCAUGUUAGGGUAAUGCUUCCUACUACUACAAAUAUGCCCCCCAAAAUAUAAUGACUCAAGCACAAUACAAGCUUAUUUCUUGUUCAUGAGACAAAGGAGAAUGUUGCUUGCUAUCAACGAGGGCUCUGUUCCGGGCUGUCAUUCAGAGACCCAGGCUGACAGCGACUCACCGCCUUCUUUCCCUAGUAAUCCUGGAUGUCCCCUCGAUGCCAGUCAGCUGGAAGGGAAAAGAGCAUGGAAGAGCACUGGCGGGAAGUUACGGGCCUGGCCUGGAAGUGGAACACAUUAGUUCUCACUUUGCACUGGCUCAGACUUCCUUACUUCAUCACACUAACCACAAGGGAAGCUGGAAAAUAUAGACUGGGAGGAAAGAAAUUUUAGUAAAUAGCUUGCAGUAUCUGCCACAUUGCCUCAAUCACAUACGAUGUAGUAACUUUACAUUUUGCUGAUGUUGAGUAGCACAAACUACUAUUUGUGAUUUGAUGGAGUCAUUUUUACUUGGGUGUGUUGACAGAGCUGAGUCAAAGUAGCUGUUCAUAUUACCGUGUAGUGGGUGUGGUGUCACAGUGUGAUACCUGCUGAAAGAGCAUUGCAUGCUCAGUCAGUGAGGCAAAGGCAGUGCUUAUUAUGCCAUAAAGGGCUGUUGGGACUUUACCAGGUAGGCGAGUAGAAGCGAGUGCAUCCUAGGUAGAAGGAACGGCGUGGCACAUUUGAGGUACAGCAAGGACUUUAGCAGGGGCCAGGGGAGAGAAUGAGAACAGGGAAGUAGAGCAGCAGAAAGAGAUGGCGUUGAAAAGAGCUGGCCAGAACCAACUCACACACAACUUUGAGAGAUGCUGGGGAGAUUGGACUUGUGCGGGGAAGAGUUGGGUGUCUAUGGAUGGUGAUGUGGGAUGAAGAAGGUAGUCAGAGAGCAGGCUUUUAAAGAGUAAUGUUAUAUUAGUAGUUUAGUAAUAUAGAGUUAGACAUUUAGUAUUUAGUAAAGUAGGUCAUAUUUAUACUUGUUGUGUCAUGGUACCUGUGGAAUGCCAUGGAAAUGUCAAAUGGACACUUCUAUGUAGCAACCUGGAGGUCAGAAGGGAGGGAGGUUGCAGAAAUAGGUCGAUGAAAGAGGUCUUGAAAGGUGGCAUGUCAACAGGAACAAAUGCCGCUGAGCUGUCAGGCAAGAUAAUGGUGGAGAGGUGGCUGUUGGAGUUAGCAUCAGAUGGCACCGGUGAUCUUGGCCAAAUCAGACAUCCAGACCAGAAUUGCAAUAGAUGGUGCAAUUGCAAUCUUAGGUUGGAUUUCCUAGAAACAGUGCCUCAGAUCUCUUGUGGAGGUGAUUUGUAAAAGUAUGCACUUCAGGAAACAUUUGUAAGGGAGGGAGCAAAGCCCAUGAGGAAGGGGAAUGCCUGAAAGGGGUAAAGCCUUGGCCUUGUGCUGGGGGAAGAGGGCUCUGUGAACUCUGCUUGUGGCAAAGGAGCUGUUUUUUUUCUUUUUUUCUUUUUGAGACGGAGUCUUGCUCUGUCGCCAGGCUAGAGUGCAGUGGUGUCAUCUCAGCUCACUUCAACCUCUGCUUCCCAGGUUCAAGCAAUUCUCCUGCCUCAGCCUCCCGAGUAGGUGGAACUACAGGCAUGCACCACCACGCCCAGCUAAUUUUUGUAUUUUUAGUAGAGACAGGGUUUCACUAUGUUGGCCAAGGUGGUCUCAAUCUCUUGACCUUGUGAUCCGCCCACCUCAGCCUCCCAAAGUGCUGGGAUUACAGGCAUGAGCCACCGCGCCCGGCUGGAGCUGGCUUUUAAACCCGGUAUCAGUCUCAGUCAGUCAGUCACUGCAGGCCAGCAUUUUACAUGGGAUGAAAGGAGGGAUGGAUGGAAGGGGUGGAGGAUACAUACCUGGUCCUUCCAGUUAAACUAUUUAAUAAAUAAUCAUGACUGAGAAUAUAAGCCUUAGAAGUACUGUUAUUGUUCUGUAAAUUUUUUAAAAACACUUUGAGGAUUCAUUGUUAUUUAUGCUCCUUGCCUUGGAGGGACAUCUUGGUUCUACAUAUGUAUAAAUGUCUAGCAGAUUGAAAAUCUGAAAUUCUUCUUUCAUUACUCUUCCCAUACAGUGCUCUUGCACUAUUCCUCUAAGAAAGCCAAAGACACAUUAUACUUGUUUUUUAGAUGAGGAAAUCAAGGUGCUGGGAAGUUUAAGAGAACUCUACAGCCAUUCAUCUAGCAUAAAAGGGCUGACGUUAGAACGCAGGCCAGGCCUUUGCCUCUUCCCUACCCCAUUCCAGUGGUUCUUGAAGUGGGAUCCAUGCCCUCCUGCAAGCAGAAUCACUUGUUAAAAAUGUAAACUCCAGGGUCCCUCUCUGGGGGCAGGGCCUGGGAUUCCACAUUUUCAAAAGCUCCUCUGUAAUUAGUGCAUACAAAGAAGACUCAUUGUCUUGGAGCAGCACCCGCUUCUUACACGGGGAGUCUGGGAUGGGAAAGAGGAAAGCAAGUCAGUGCAACUUGCACAUGUCUUAUCACAAACCAUAGGGAAGGAGGUGCCUUGUGGUAUAAAUACUGAGUUUAAUGCCAUUAAUAUAAACGCUCAUAUUCCCAAACAGACUGCCUGUACUAGUACAUUACUUCCAUUUUCCAAAAAAGGAAAAGAAAGGUUCCGUGUCAAAGAACUCAAUUGGAAUCCUCGCUUGGUACUUGCUUCCUUGCCAGCAGUGCUCAAAAAGAGAAAAAGAAAAUCCAAAGUCCAUGUACAUAAAAGUUCCAUUCCCGAUGGUGGAGGGCUUAAUUAAAGUCCUCAGAUGUUUCUGUGCACCUUGGAAAACAUUUUUAUGAAAUUCAUAUAUUACCAGAAGUGGCUCCAACAAUUCUUGCAGUUAAAAACCUUGUAACUCAUGCAGCUCCAUCAGGAGCAAGCUGCCUUUUUCAAGAUUUGUUUUGCUGCUUCCUUUACCUCCGUAGCCUGUGGCAGUGACGGCUGCUCAAGGGCCUUAACUGCCAGGAUGGCACUAGAGGAUUUUCCAAGGUUAAGGUCAGAUAACAGAAUCUGGAAGAAAUGGAUCCCUCUUCCUGCAUUUCCUUUUCUCAUUAUUUCAAUAAAUGCAUUGAAGGCUUGUGAUGUGUCUGGCACUACAGCAGGCACUGAGGAUGCCACGCUGAACAAAGCGGCUGGAUCUUCAUGGGGCUCAUAUCCUAGAGGGAAAGACAUAAUAAGCAGACUCUGCAGUGUCACACAACAUCACCUAGGAAAUAUAGAGAUGCAAGUGCUCAGGCGCCAGGCCAGACGUGAAUUCAACUGUGGUAGCAAGACCUUGUAUCUUCUGAUGGGACGUUGAAGUGUGAGAACCACUGGACUCUCAUAUGGUGAUAAACUUUGGAGAAAAAGGACGGAGGCAGGUGUGUUGCUGAUGCCAGCAAAUGUUAGAAUAGUGAAACUGCUACACCCUGGACUAUGAAGCAAGCCAGAUUUGAAUCCCAGCUCUGCUACUUACAAGCUGUGUAACCUCCGGCAGGCUACUUAAUCUCUCUGUACCUUGGGUUCUCCUGAGAAAUGGAGAUAAUAAUAGUAGCUAUCUUAUAGAGAUGUGAGGAUUAAAGGAACUAAUGAAUAUGAAAGUGCUGAGAAUAGAUUCUCACAUAUAGCAAACAAUAUACUUGUUGGGAGACAAUUCUCUGGACAAUUCUUGCAUUUCUACACGUCUUGGAAGCAAGGCACUAAGUACCCUUUUGUUCCAAACUAUCUUUGCAAGGAUGUUUGUAUAUAACAUCCUUGGAAGAUUGAGAUAGUGUCUCACUCUAGAGCAAAGAACAGACAUGCUUACUCCCAUUACAAAAGAUUCGGUUUCCUAACUCAGAGUUCCUGUUCUUGAAUGAAAGUCAUGCAGUAUACAGGUGUCUUUUGGCCCUCUUAACUGUCAUACUGUAGGAAUCAAUGCAAAAAUGCUGAUGGCUAUUUCUGUUGUGAGUAAAUGUCUGAACUGAGAGUCUAGUGUCUUCUAUCAGCAUUUGUAAAACUGGCCAACUGACUUGCUAAGUUGCAAGUAGGGUGAAAUCUCAGACCCUUCGUAGUCCUUGACAAUUCUGUGAAAGUGUGUAAGUGUUUGUUAGUACUAAUGUUGUUAUUACUCCACAGUACGUGCCAAUUUUCUGGAAGAAACAAAAAUGUAAUUGAUGGCCCUAGCCUUCAAAGAGUUCCCAGUUGAGCCAAGGAGGUUAAAUAUGCGAAGAUGACGCAAAAGACAUACAGCAGCAGGAAAGCAAAGCUUUGGAAUGAAACUUGGGUUUGAAUGUAGGCUGUGGAUGCUCACCAGCUAUGGCAACUCUGAGCCUCAACAAAUUUCUAUUUGUAAAGUGCUGUUGUUAAUAAUGCUUACUGUGUGAGGUUGUGAACAUUAAGAUAGUGCAUGGAGAGAGCUUAGCACGGGUCUGGCAUGCAGUAAGCACUCAGUUACCAUUACUGAUGUUGCUGUAUUGCAUUUGUGCUUAGGAUACAAGCAGAGCACUUUCUCUCCCCUCCCUGGGUCUUUAGGGAAGUAAGGCCCCAGUACUGUACUUCCUUUCAGGUGGAAGCUGCUUUCCUUGGAACCACCAAACCCCAACUCAGUAUGUCCCUGGAUUCUGCCCAAAGAAUUCCCCAGGGCUAAGCUCCUAUAGGUGGGUGGCUAAAGGACUGGCUUCAGAGUCAGACAGCUCUCAGUGGAUAUAUACUUAGAGAUUUAAUAUGAUAUAUACUGCUUUGAAGUUUAUGUGGUUUUUGAUGAUUUUAUUAAUGUGCAUAAUAGUCCUAGCAUAUAAUAUGUGUUCAGCCAAUGUUAAUCAGUGCCCUAGGCUACACCACCAUGAUCUAAUGGGCCAUUCAAUUUUCAUGACUGUAUUCCUAGGAUAUUUCUCAAUGACUCAUACAUGGUAGGUGUUCAGUAAAUAUUUGUUGAUUUAAUUGGCUUGAGUGAACAAAAGAAGUAAUACGUCCUUUCAUCUUUUCUUUCAAGAUAUUUCUGCAUUAAAUCAUCCUCAGUAUAUUUUUUUGAAAGCCAAGUUUUCCCAAAGCUCCUCAUUUCCUCAUCUCCCUCUGUGCCACUGGUUUUUCAGUUGCUGGGGGCUACAGACCCUCUCUCUAGAAAGAUGGACAUGUGAACAUAAGCACUGCAUUUUGCACACAAUUUCCGUGGUUCAGAAACCACCUGAACUUUUCCUUCUAGAGGACCCUGCUUAAACACUUCCAUUCUAGGGUGUCCAGCCCAUUAAGAUGGCCAAGAAAUCACAUCCCACUCAUCUCCCCCAAAUCAGCAAGCUGUCAUGGACGGUCCUCAAUACAGUUGCUACUUUGUUCCUCUAUAAUCAAGGCCACACAAGACCCACUUCCAAUCUACUUGUGAUUUAGGGAUAGCAAAGGAUUAAAGCAAUUCAAGUAUUUUAGAUUCCUAUUGAUAGCAGAAUUGUGGUUUUCAAGACGUGCUAAUGGAAAAAUUGUUAGUAAAAAUAGGUUCAUGCAGUCUUAUUGAUCAUGCUUGUAAUUCUGAAGAUUCCACUUGUACUUUUUGUAACCAUAUUUCUCUUCUCUUCCAUUCUCUAGUUGUGAGAAAACCCAGUUGUCCAAUAAUUGUCAAGCUUUCCUCGGCCUUAGGGAAUGAGCACUCAAGACCUUUCUGGGCCAAGUGUGGUCGCCGACUCCUGUAAUCCUAGCACUUUGGGAGGCCGAGGAGGGAGAGCUGCUUGAGCCUAGGAGUUCAAGACUAGCCUGAGCAACAGCAGGACUUCAUCACUACAAAAAAUAAAAAAUUAGCCAUAUGUGGUGGUACACCCCUGUAGUCCCCCAGCUACUCGGGAGGCUAAGGUGGGAGGAUUACUUAAACCCGAGAGGUCGAGGCUGCAGUGAGCCGUGAUCGCACCACUGCAGUCCAGCCUGACCCUGUCUCAAAAAAAAAAAAAAAAAAAAAACCUUCUGGAAGCAGAAAGGAGGAGGUUUUCCAAAACCAAAUCAUGUCAAGUACCUAGCUUGACCUCAAAAAAAAAUACAGAAGCAGGGUUGGUAAUUGAUUGACAGGAAGGGCAGCUCAAAGCAGGAAAUGGAGAGUGGUAUGAAAACACUUAAGCAGUACUGCCCAAAGGAAGAACCUGAAAAGUUCAGCCAUAGAUUUUCUGAGAAGAUGAAAGUGUAGGCAUUAGCAUACUCAAGAAUCAGGCAGACAGUUUUCCCCAUUUGGAAGCUGAAAAAGGAAUGAUCUGCUGCCCAAGACAAGAAAAUGAUGUGGGCCCAGAGGGAACCGUCACUCACACGUACACUGUCCAGGGGGCCAGAGAAGGAUUACAGCCGCCAUUUUGGCUUCUCUAGAGUGAAGCAGCAAAACAAUGUCUAGUGGUUGCUAGGCAACCAUUAGUCCAUCGCUGCCCUUUUCCAUUAAACAUUAUCUGCCUUCUUAGAUUGUUUUAUUUUUUUAAACAGGAUAGGUAAUGCAACAGAGAAUUAACGGUGCAACCUAACAAUGAAAACGCAUUUGAGGUUCCCGAAUCAGUGAAGGCUUUGCAAAGGUUAGAUCACUCUUGGGUGGAUGCCGAAGAUAGUGACAGUUGACUGAAACCUCUUCCCCAGACAUUUCAUCACUGGUCCUCAUGUUUCCUAGUGCCAAAAAUAAUAAUGUGGACGUAACAAUAAUCUCUGUACAUUGUAAAAUGUCUGUCCUCUGCUACGACCUGCUCCAAGCUAGAUCUUGUCCUGAAGCAAGUUUCUCUAUCGGCAAAGAGUGGAUGUCAGAGGUGGUAAAAUGGAGUUCUAGCCCUGGUCAGCUUUGCAGAUAGCUAAGAUCAUGGUAUCCAAAGAACCUGAGCAAAAGUACAUGGAAAUAACACCUGUUUAUGCAAGGAACGCUUUCUGACACAUAAAAAUGAAGAGUAACUGGUAGGAGAGAAUAAGCGUCUUUAUUCAGAUACACAUCGCAUUCGGAUUUUAAACAUACCUAAUGACUUUUACAACAAGAGGACACUGAGGUACCCAGAAAGAGGGUGGAAAAUCAGGAUGAAGGGAGUUACUGCUAGCCUGUCAUGUACCAUGCACACAACCUAUCUUUUUAAAUACCAGUGGAUUUCCUGUCUGGCUCAGGGGGCCUGUCUAGGAAGAGAUUCAAGGAAAGUAGAUGGGUUAGUUCCAGGGACUGGGGCUCAAAAAUUUAAAGCCACACGUAACGUUAGCUCUCUCACUCCCACACACAUUUAAGAUAAAGGAGAUGGCAGUAGUGUGCUGCCCAGAGGAUGGAAUACGCAGAUAACUAGGUUUCUAUACUGGUUCUACUCACUAGUCUGAUCUUGGGUAAUUUUUUGGGUCAUUGUUCUGUAAGGGAGGGCAAUAAUAACUACUUGGUCAGGGCUGUUGUGACAAUUCAGCAAUAAAACAUGGUCAAUUGCAGCUAA